GCUCUUAUCGGUUCCCAUCCCAGUUGUUGAUCUUAUGCAAGACGCUGCACGACCCCGCGCCCGCUUGUCGCCACGGCACUUGAGGCAGCCGGAGAUACUCUGAGUUACUCGGAGCCCGACGCCUGAGGGUGAGAUGAACGCGCUGGCCUCCCUAACCGUCCGGACCUGUGAUCGCUUCUGGCAGACCGAACCGGCGCUCCUGCCCCCGGGGUGACGCGCAGCUCCCAGCCGCCCAGACACAUGGCCCCAGGCCAAGCACCCCAUCAGGCUACCCCGUGGAGGGAUGCCCACCCUUUCUUCCUCCUGUCCCCAGUGAUGGGCCUCCUCAGCCGCGCCUGGAGCCGCCUGAGGGGCCUGGGACCUCUAGAGCCCUGGCUGGUGGAAGCAGUAAAAGGAGCAGCUCUGGUAGAAGCUGGCCUGGAGGGAGAAGCUAGGACUCCUCUGGCAAUCCCCCAUACCCCUUGGGGCAGACGCCCUGAAGAGGAGGCUGAAGACAGUGGAGGCCCUGGAGAGGACAGAGAAACACUGGGGCUGAAAACCAGCAGUUCCCUUCCUGAAGCCUGGGGACUUUUGGAUGAUGAUGAUGGCAUGUAUGGUGAGCGAGAGGCAACCAGUGUCCCUAGAGGGCAGGGAAGUCAAUUUGCAGAUGGCCAGCGUGCUCCCCUGUCUCCCAGCCUUCUGAUAAGGACACUGCAAGGUUCUGAUAAGAACCCAGGGGAGGAGAAAGCCGAGGAAGAGGGAGUUGCUGAAGAGGAGGGAGUUAACAAGUUCUCUUAUCCACCAUCACACCGGGAGUGUUGUCCAGCCGUGGAGGAGGAGGACGAUGAAGAAGCUGUAAAGAAAGAAGCUCACAGAACCUCUACUUCUGCCUUGUCUCCAGGAUCCAAGCCCAGCACUUGGGUGUCUUGCCCAGGGGAGGAAGAGAAUCAAGCCACGGAGGAUAAAAGAACAGAAAGAAGUAAAGGAGCCAGGAAGACCUCCGUGUCCCCCCGAUCUUCAGGCUCCGACCCCAGGUCCUGGGAGUAUCGUUCAGGAGAGGCGUCCGAGGAGAAGGAGGAAAAGGCACACAAAGAAACUGGGAAAGGAGAAGCUGCCCCAGGGCCGCAAUCCUCAGCCCCAGCCCAGAGGCCCCAGCUCAAGUCCUGGUGGUGCCAACCCAGUGAUGAAGAGGAGGGUGAGGUCAAGGCUUUGGGGGCAGCUGAGAAGGAUGGAGAAGCUGAGUGUCCUCCCUGCAUCCCCCCACCAAGUGCCUUCCUGAAGGCCUGGGUGUAUUGGCCAGGAGAGGACACAGAGGAAGAGGAAGAUGAGGAAGAAGAUGAGGACAGUGACUCUGGAUCAGAUGAGGAAGAGGGAGAAGCUGAGGCUUCCUCUUCCACUCCUGCUACAGGUGUCUUCUUGAAGUCCUGGGUCUAUCAGCCAGGAGAGGACACAGAGGAGGAGGAAGAUGAGGACAGUGAUACAGGAUCAGCCGAGGAUGAAAGAGAAGCUGAGACUUCUGCUUCCACACCCCCUGCAAGUGCUUUCUUGAAGGCCUGGGUGUAUCGGCCAGGAGAGGACACGGAGGAGGAGGAAGAUGAGGAUGUGGAUAGUGAGGAUAAGGAAGAUGAUUCAGAAGCAGCCUUGGGAGAAGCUGAGUCAGACCCACAUCCCUCCCACCCGGACCAGAGGGCCCACUUCAGGGGCUGGGGAUAUCGACCUGGAAAAGAGACAGAGGAAGAGGAAGCUGCUGAGGACUGGGGAGAAGCUGAGCCCUGCCCCUUCCGAGUGGCCAUCUAUGUACCUGGAGAGAAGCCACCGCCUCCCUGGGCUCCUCCUAGGCUGCCCCUCCGACUGCAAAGGCGGCUCAAGCGCCCAGAAACCCCUACUCAUGAUCCGGACCCUGAGACUCCCCUAAAGGCCAGAAAGGUGCGCUUCUCCGAGAAGGUCACUGUCCAUUUCCUGGCUGUCUGGGCAGGGCCGGCCCAGGCCGCCCGCCAGGGCCCCUGGGAGCAGCUUGCUCGGGAUCGCAGCCGCUUCGCACGCCGCAUCACCCAGGCCCAGGAGGAGCUGAGCCCCUGCCUCACCCCUGCUGCCCGGGCCAGAGCCUGGGCACGCCUCAGGAACCCACCUUUAGCCCCCAUCCCUGCCCUCACCCAGACCUUGCCUUCCUCCUCUGUCCCUUCGUCCCCAGUCCAGACCACGCCCUUGAGCCAAGCUGUGGCCACACCUUCCCGCUCGUCUGCUGCUGCAGCGGCUGCCCUGGACCUCAGUGGGAGGCGUGGCUGAGACCAACUGGUUUGCCUAUAAUUUAUUAACUAUUUAUUUUUUCUAAGUGUGGGUUUAUAUAAGGAAUAAAGCCUUUUGAUUUGUA